GGAGUCGACAAUAACAAACCAAGCCGCGGCGGUGUCCGCGGCCCUGCCGAGCCCUCGGCGUUGCCUCAGAAUCCCCCAGUCGCCUGGGCCCCUCGGCUCUGACAGGCCGCGGCCUUCUGUCCCCCGGCCCCAGACCCAGAGCCGAGGGGCCUGCUCGCGUCCUUGUCCGCCCGGACCCCUCCCUGCCUCCUAGAGUUCGGGGCCGCGGCGGGCGGGCGCCCGGGACGCCGGCGGUUGUGUCGGCUUAGCGGUGCCGAAUGGGCGGUUGGUAACCGCUGCCGAGGACUAGGCGGCGGCGGAAGAUGGUGCCGGGGGUCGCUGGCUCUGCUGCUGCCGCCGGCGAAGGAGGAGGCGUUGCCGGUUUUCUGAGUUUAACCAGUAAUGCCAUUCAGUUGCCAAUCUCAAGCAAAGCAAACAUAAGCCAGUUUUAAUCUACUUUUUAAGAAAAGUGGUAGUCCUUUUCACAGUGCCUGACGUAACUGUAUCAGAGGGUGAGGUAUAAGCUCACAGAAUUCAGAUAAAUCAUCAUGAAGUUAUAUGUAUUUCUGGUUAACACUGGAACUACUCUAACAUUUGACACUGAACUUACAGUGCAAACUGUGGCAGACCUUAAGCAUGCCAUUCAAAGCAAAUACAAGAUUGCUAUUCAACACCAGGUGCUGGUGGUCAAUGGAGGAGAAUGCAUGGCUGCAGAUCGAAGAGUGUGUACCUACAGUGCUGGGACGGAUACAAAUCCAAUUUUUCUUUUUAACAAAGAAAUGAUCUUAUGUGAUCGUCCACCUGCUAUUCCUAAAACUACCUUUUCGACAGAAAAUGACAUGGAAAUAAAAGUUGAAGAAUCUCUUAUGAUGCCUGCAGUUUUUCAUACUGUUGCUUCAAGGACACAGCUUGCAUUGGAAAUGUAUGAAGUUGCCAAGAAACUUUGUUCUUUUUGUGAAGGUCUUGUACAUGAUGAACAUCUUCAACACCAAGGCUGGGCUGCAAUCAUGGCCAACCUGGAGGACUGUUCAAAUUCAUACCAAAAGCUACUUUUCAAGUUUGAAAGUAUUUAUUCAAAUUAUCUGCAGUCCAUAGAAGACAUCAAGUUAAAACUUACUCAUUUAGGAACUGCAGUUUCAGUAAUGGCCAAGAUUCCACUGUUGGAGUGCCUAACCAGACAUAGUUACAGAGAAUGUUUGGGAAGACUGGAUUCUUUACCUGAACAUGAAGACUCAGAAAAAGCUGAGAUGAAAAGAUCCACUGAACUGGUGCUCUCUCCUGAUAUGCCUAGAACAACUAACGAAUCUUUGUUAACCUCAUUUCCCAAGUCAGUGGAACAUGUGUCCCCAGAUACCGCAGAUGCUGAAAGUGGCAAAGAAAUUAGGGAAUCUUGUCAAAGUACUGUUCAUCAGCAAGAUGAAACUACGAUUGACACUAAAGAUGGUGAUCUGCCCUUUUUUAAUGUCUCUUUGUUAGACUGGAUAAAUGUUCAAGAUAGACCUAAUGAUGUGGAAUCUUUGGUCAGGAAGUGCUUUGAUUCUAUGAGCAGGCUUGAUCCAAGGAUUAUUCGACCAUUUAUAGCAGAAUGCCGUCAAACUAUUGCCAAACUUGAUAAUCAGAAUAUGAAAGCCAUUAAAGGACUUGAAGAUCGGCUCUACGCCCUGGACCAGAUGAUUGCUAGCUGUGGCCGACUGGUGAAUGAACAGAAAGAGCUUGCUCAGGGAUUUUUAGCUAAUCAGAAGAGAGCUGAAAACUUAAAGGAUGCAUCUGUAUUACCUGAUUUAUGCCUGAGUCACGCAAAUCAGUUGAUGAUUAUGUUGCAAAAUCAUAGAAAACUGUUAGAUAUUAAGCAGAAGUGUACCACUGCCAAACAAGAACUAGCAAAUAACCUACAUGUCAGACUGAAGUGGUGUUGCUUUGUAAUGCUUCAUGCUGAUCAAGAUGGAGAGAAGUUACAAGCUUUGCUCCGCCUCGUAAUAGAGCUGUUAGAAAGAGUCAAAAUUGUUGAAGCUCUUAGUACAGUUCCUCAGAUGUACUGCUUAGCUGUUGUUGAGGUUGUAAGAAGAAAAAUGUUCAUAAAACACUACAGGGAGUGGGCUGGUGCUUUAGUCAAAGAUGGAAAGAGAUUAUAUGAAGCAGAAAAAUCAAAAAGGGAAUCCUUUGGGAAAUUAUUUAGGAAGUCUUUUUUAAGAAAUCGUCUGUUUAGGGGACUGGACUCCUGGCCCCCUUCCUUUUGUACUCAAAAGCCUCGAAAGUUUGACUGUGAACUUCCAGAUAUUUCAUUAAAAGAUUUACAGUUUCUGCAAUCAUUUUGUCCUUCGGAAGUUCAGCCAUUCCUCAGGGUUCCCUUACUUUGUGACUUUGAACCUCUACACCAGCAUGUACUUGCUCUACAUAAUUUGGUAAAAGCAGCACAAAGUUUGGAUGAAAUGUCACAGACCAUUACAGAUCUACUGAGUGAACAAAAGGCAUCUGUGAGUCAGACAUCCCCACAGUCUGCUUCUUCACCAAGGAUGGAAAGUACAGCAGGAAUUACAACUACUACCUCACCGAGAACUCCUCCACCACUGACUGUUCAGGAUCCCUUAUGUCCUGCAGUUUGUCCCUUAGAAGAAUUAUCUCCAGAUAGUAUUGAUGCACAUACGUUUGAUUUUGAAACUAUUCCCCAUCCAAACAUAGAACAGACUAUUCACCAAGUUUCUUUAGACUUGGAUUCAUUAGCAGAAAGUCCUGAAUCAGAUUUUAUGUCUGCUGUGAAUGAGUUUGUAAUAGAAGAAAAUUUGUCGUCUCCUAAUCCUAUAAGUGAUCCACAAAGCCCAGAAAUGAUGGUGGAAUCACUUUAUUCAUCAGUUAUCAAUGCGAUAGACAGUAGACGAAUGCAGGAUACAAAUGUAUGUGGUAAGGAGGAUUUUGGAGAUCAUACUUCUCUGAAUGUCCAGUUGGAAAGAUGUAGAGUUGUUGCCCAAGACUCUCACUUCAGUAUACAAACCAUUAAGGAAGACCUUUGCCACUUUAGAACAUUUGUACAAAAAGAACAGUGUGACUUCUCAAAUUCAUUAAAAUGUACAGCAGUAGAAAUAAGAAACAUUAUUGAAAAAGUAAAAUGUUCUCUGGAAAUAACACUAAAAGAAAAACAUCAAAAAGAACUACUGUCUUUAAAAAAUGAAUAUGAAGGUAAACUUGACGGACUAAUAAAGGAAACUGAAGAGAAUGAAAACAAAAUUAAAAAAUUGAAGGGAGAGUUAGUAUGCCUUGAGGAGGUUUUACAAAAUAAAGAUAAUGAAUUUGCUUUGGUUAAACAUGAAAAAGAAGCUGUAAUCUGCCUGCAGAAUGAAAAGGAUCAGAAGUUGUUAGAGAUGGAAAAUAUAAUGCACUCUCAAAAUUGUGAAAUUAAAGAACUGAAGCAGUCACGAGAAAUAGUGUUAGAAGACUUAAAAAAGCUCCAUGUUGAAAAUGAUGAGAAGUUACAGUUAUUGAGGGCAGAACUUCAGUCCUUGGAGCAAAGUCAUCUAAAGGAAUUAGAGGACACACUUCAGGUUAGGCACAUACAAGAGUUUGAGAAGGUUAUGACAGACCACAGAGUUUCUUUGGAGGAAUUAAAAAAGGAAAACCAACAAAUAAUUAAUCAAAUACAAGAAUCUCAUGCUGAAAUUAUCCAGGAAAAAGAAAAACAGUUACAGGAAUUAAAACUCAAGGUUUCUGAUUUGUCAGACACGAGAUGCAAGUUAGAGGUUGAACUUGCGUUGAAGGAAGCAGAAACUGAUGAAAUAAAAAUUUUGCUGGAAGAAAGCAGAGCCCAGCAGAAGGAGACCUUGAAAUCUCUUCUUGAACAAGAGACAGAAAAUUUGAGAACAGAAAUUAGUAAACUCAACCAAAAGAUUCAGGAUAAUAAUGAAAAUUAUCAGGUGGGCUUAGCAGAGCUAAGAACUUUAAUGACAAUUGAAAAAGAUCAGUGUAUUUCCGAGUUAAUUAGUAGACAUGAAGAAGAAUCUAAUAUACUUAAAGCUGAAUUAAACAAAGUAACAUCUUUGCAUAACCAAGCAUUUGAAAUAGAAAAAAACCUAAAAGAACAAAUAAUUGAACUGCAGAGUAAAUUGGAUUCAGAAUUGAGUGCUCUUGAAAGACAAAAAGAUGAAAAAAUUACCCAACAAGAAGAGAAAUACGAAGCUAUUAUCCAGAACCUUGAGAAAGACAGACAAAAAUUGGUCAGCAGCCAGGAGCAAGACAGAGAACAGUUAAUUCAGAAGCUUAAUUGUGAAAAAGAUGAAGCUAUUCAGACUGCCCUAAAAGAAUUUAAAUUGGAGAGAGAAGUUGUUGAGAAAGAGUUAUUAGAAAAAGUUAAACAUCUUGAGAAUCAAAUAGCAAAAAGGUACCAGCAGUUUGAUCAUCAGUGCCAAUAUCAACAAGGUGAAAAAGGCAACACUUGGUGUUACUAUGAAAACAGUUCUGACUUCACUUGUCCUCUGAAUGUGUUUGGUUAACCCCAGGCUUCUAUGGAUCACUCUUUGGGAAUCAUUAGCCUAAAGAAAUGGUUGGCAAACUUUUAUAAAGGCCCAGAUAGUAAGUAGUUUAAGUUUUGUGGGCCAAAUGGCCUCUAUCCAAACUACCCAACUGUACCAUUUUAGCAAGACAGCAGUGAGACUAUAUAAAUGAAUGGUUUUGGCUGUGUUCCGCAAAAAAGCGGAUUGGAUUUACCUGCCCUUGAUCUAGAGUAUCUCAUUUUGCCAUCUCAUUUUCAUUUAAUGUUGGUUAUUCUUAAGUCUACUUUCCAGGCAGUCAACUUGGCAAAGUGUUAAUAGCCAAUAUUGAGUCUGGAAUCUGUGGUCAUUACACCCGUAUAAAUAAUUUUGGCCUCACUCCACAUUGUCCCUCCUCUUGUAACUGUCAUUAGAUCUAUUCCCAUAUGUAUUUUCCAUUUUUCUGCCAAAAUAUAUUAAAGAUUCUGUAAUUGCUUUGCAAUUCCUUCUUUGUUAGAUUUUUAACUCUCCAGAGAUCUGGCAAUUUGAGUGUAGCAAUGAGUAUGGAAGUAAUUAAAUGGUGGGAGAGGUUGUUGAAAAGGAUCAUCUCAUUGAGAAGAGGACUACCUCAAGUGAAGGGACACUGAUUUCCUCAGACAAGGUAGAAAAAGGCUGUUGCUUCCAGGAAGGAAGGUUUGGUGGGAUUUGGAGGCACAGCUGGGACAUGUCUCAAAGCCUUGCCUUCCUUAGUCACUGGUUUUUCAAACAACUACAAGUGUGUACUGUUAUGCCAUGUACUGCCCUGGUUUUCCAGUGUUCUAUUUUGCACUGGCACUGAGGUCAUUACUGCUUUCAGAUCAGAGAAUUAAUCUCAGUUUCCAUGUUUUAUGGGAUUUUUUUUUCCUCUAGAGUCAUUUUUUUGUAUCAGGAUUGAGCUUAUAAAACAACCACUUUUAAAUAUUUCAGGAUUAAAGGGAUUAAUACUAGAUUUAGAGUUUACAUGAAUGUUGGGAGAACUAGGAGACUGGAUAGUAAUCUGGUGAAGGCCAAGAGAUCUAUAAUAGAAAGUCAUCUGAAGCACCAAAGUUGGUGGCUUAGGAAACUGAUACAGUUCUUUGAAGACUUUCGUCAGUUGUCUACCAAGACCCCCAAACAGGUGGUUUACUUGGAAGUCUCUUACGAAUCUCACAUUGCCCACAUGUUUGGCUACAACCACCUCCAGAGUCUCUCUCUUCAGCAUCCCAGGUCAGGUGUGGGUAUCUUGCAUUGGCAAUCUCAAACAUAGAACCUACCGAGGAGGGAAUUCUGGAUAAUAUCCCUGGCUUCUCUGUCAUGCAGAGGAAACCUUUGAAGAAGAAAGAUGCUUAUGUGAGGACACACAGUCCGGCAUAUUUCCCUUUCACCACUUGGUUCUACAUAUGCCAGAAGCAACACUGAGGGGCCAGCUGCCAAGGAGAAACAUUUCUAAGAUAUGUAUAUUAGCUAUGUCUGUAGCUCCCACAGUAAGUCAAUAAGAAAAAGGCACAUAAUCUGUUAGAAAAAUGGACAGAGGAUAUGAAGAGAUCAAAGAAGAAAUACAAAUGGCCAACAUGUAGAUACUGUUCGGUCCACUUGUGAUUAAGGAAAUGCAAGAUCAGAAUAUCUUCUAUUUAAUUUGGAAUUAUUAAAGUUUAUAUUAGUUUUGAAAUGUUUAGUUUUGAAAAUAUAGGAGAAAGCUUUCUCCUGUACCUUUGUACAAAGAAAUAAGAGUGGAACGUGUGUAUGUGGUUUGCGUGGGUUGGGAAAUCUACCUACUACAUGAUUGAUGGCCUUGCUCCCAGGAAGUAGUGAUGUGGAUCUGAGUGAGUAUGGGUGGGAGCAUUUUAAUUUUGUAAUUCUAAUUUCAAAAGAGAUUUUUAUUUUAUUAUUUUUUUGAGACGGAGUCUCACUCUGUUGCCCAGGCUGGAGUGCAGUGGCAUGAUCUCGGCUUACUGCCACCUCUGCCUCCAGGGUUCAAGUGAUAGAAGAGAUUUUUUUGAAAAAACAGUGAACUAAUUGUUUACUAGGCCCCAUUUUAAUUCAGUCAGUGUUAAGAGUUCAAGCAUCAAGACAAUCUAGUUUAUGUUCAAUGUAAAUUUUCUAGUUGCUAGAAAUAUUUGGAUAUAAUACAGUCCUUUGCUAGAACUGACAUUUUAAUGGUGGGAAAAACUGUCAGCCUUUAGAGAUGCCUUUUUUCAAGUUUCCGUGAUACUAAAGUUCCCAGCUGGUAACAAAUGUAUCUGCUUCCUUGAGUUUCAAUGUCCAGGCCUCUUUAAAGUAUUCAGGUAUGCAAAGACAGGAUUAUGCAAGUUUCUUUUAGUUGGACAACCUUUAUUGAUGAAUUUCUUAGGUUUCUGUGGUAGUGUUGUUAGAUUAAAUACAGUCAUUCCCUCUUGUCUAGUUUCGUUUUAUGUGAUUUCGCUCUUAUGGUUUCACUUACCCCAUGGUUCGAAAGUAUUAAAUGAAAUAAACAAUUCCUGAGUUUUAAAUUGGA